AGGCCGGCUCGGAGGCAGCGAGAAAGCGCAGCCAGGCGGCUGCUCGGCGUUCUCUCAGGUGACUGCUCGGAGUUCUCCCAGUUUCUCUUUUAACAGUGUUUGGUGUUGCAAGCAGGAUCCAAAGGAGACCUAUAGUGACUCCCAGGAGCUCUUAGUGACCAAGUGAAGGUACCUGUGGGGCUCAUUGUGCCCAUUGCUCUUUCACUGCUUUCAACUGGUAGUUGUGGCAUGCUACUCCUGGAGUUUCAUUCAGUGAAUGAGAACUAUAGUUUGGUUCUGUGAGAUCUCUAUGAAUCAAGGCGGCCACUGAAGCGGAGAAAAGAAAUGCUUAAAUGUUAAGAAAGUUUGAAGUGCAGAAAAAGGUGAUUGUAAAUCCAUAUGGUUAAGCUUAGCCCAUUUCUUAAAAGGCUUGAUUGCUCAUUCCUCCAUUCAUUGAUUUACUCACUCUUCCAAUCCAUGUUAUUGAGUCUUGCUCUGUAAUUCCGGAUGGUUGUGCUUUUAAGUACUGCAUAGUGGUUGUAUGUCUGUGUUAGCAUUGCUGAAUGUAUCAGGGAAUUCAUUUUUUUAUCCCCAUUCAUUCGUUCCAUUCAUCUGUUUCUCUCUCUCUCUCUCUUUGUGUGUGUGUGUGUGUGUGUGUGUGUGUGUGUGUGUGUGUGUGUUAUGCCUAGAAAACAUUUCUCAAGAAUUAGAAUUACGAUAUGCUGUCAAACACAAUGACUUAUUUGAACCUCUUUUAUUUGUAGGUUGAAGCACUGGACAAUGCCACAUACUUUGUGGAUGGUGUGGGUCUUGGGGGUCAUCAUCAGCCUCUCCAAGGAAGAAUCCUCCAAUCAGGCUUCUCUGUCUUGUGACCGCAAUGGUAUCUGCAAGGGCAGCUCAGGAUCUUUAAACUCCAUUCCCUCAGGGCUCACAGAAGCUGUAAAAAGCCUUGACCUGUCCAACAACAGGAUCACCUACAUUAGCAACAGUGACCUACAGAGGUGUGUGAACCUCCAGGCUCUGGUGCUGACAUCCAAUGGAAUUAACACAAUAGAGGAAGAUUCUUUUUCUUCCCUGGGCAGUCUUGAACAUUUAGACUUAUCCUAUAAUUACUUAUCUAAUUUAUCGUCUUCCUGGUUCAAGCCCCUUUCUUCUUUAACAUUCUUAAACUUACUGGGAAAUCCUUACAAAACCCUAGGGGAAACAUCUCUUUUUUCUCAUCUCACAAAAUUGCAAAUCCUGAGAGUGGGAAAUAUGGACACCUUCACUAAGAUUCAAAGAAAAGAUUUUGCUGGACUUACCUUCCUUGAGGAACUUGAGAUUGAUGCUUCAGAUCUACAGAGCUAUGAGCCAAAAAGUUUGAAGUCAAUUCAGAAUGUAAGUCAUCUGAUCCUUCAUAUGAAGCAGCAUAUUUUACUGCUGGAGAUUUUUGUAGAUGUUACAAGUUCCGUGGAAUGUUUGGAACUGCGAGAUACUGAUUUGGACACUUUCCAUUUUUCAGAACUAUCCACUGGUGAAACAAAUUCAUUGAUUAAAAAGUUUACAUUUAGAAAUGUGAAAAUCACCGAUGAAAGUUUGUUUCAGGUUAUGAAACUUUUGAAUCAGAUUUCUGGAUUGUUAGAAUUAGAGUUUGAUGACUGUACCCUUAAUGGAGUUGGUAAUUUUAGAGCAUCUGAUAAUGACAGAGUUAUAGAUCCAGGUAAAGUGGAAACGUUAACAAUCCGGAGGCUGCAUAUUCCAAGGUUUUACUUAUUUUAUGAUCUGAGCACUUUAUAUUCACUUACAGAAAGAGUUAAAAGAAUCACAGUAGAAAACAGUAAAGUUUUUCUGGUUCCUUGUUUACUUUCACAACAUUUAAAAUCAUUAGAAUACUUGGAUCUCAGUGAAAAUUUGAUGGUUGAAGAAUACUUGAAAAAUUCAGCCUGUGAGGAUGCCUGGCCCUCUCUACAAACUUUAAUUUUAAGGCAAAAUCAUUUGGCAUCAUUGGAAAAAACCGGAGAGACUUUGCUCACUCUGAAAAACUUGACUAACAUUGAUAUCAGUAAGAAUAGUUUUCAUUCUAUGCCUGAAACUUGUCAGUGGCCAGAAAAGAUGAAAUAUUUGAACUUAUCCAGCACACGAAUACACAGUGUAACAGGCUGCAUUCCCAAGACACUGGAAAUUUUAGAUGUUAGCAACAACAAUCUCAAUUUAUUUUCUUUGAAUUUGCCGCAACUCAAAGAACUUUAUAUUUCCAGAAAUAAGUUGAUGACUCUACCAGAUGCCUCCCUCUUACCCAUGUUACUAGUAUUGAAAAUCAGUAGGAAUGCAAUAACUACGUUUUCUAAGGAGCAACUUGACUCAUUUCACACACUGAAGACUUUGGAAGCUGGUGGCAAUAACUUCAUUUGCUCCUGUGAAUUCCUCUCCUUCACUCAGGAGCAGCAAGCACUGGCCAAAGUCUUGAUUGAUUGGCCAGCAAAUUACCUGUGUGACUCUCCAUCCCAUGUGCGUGGCCAGCAGGUUCAGGAUGUCCGCCUCUCGGUGUCGGAAUGUCACAGGACAGCACUGGUGUCUGGCAUGUGCUGUGCUCUGUUCCUGCUGAUCCUGCUCACGGGGGUCCUGUGCCACCGUUUCCAUGGCCUGUGGUAUAUGAAAAUGAUGUGGGCCUGGCUCCAGGCCAAAAGGAAGCCCAGGAAAGCUCCCAGCAGGAACAUCUGCUAUGAUGCAUUUGUUUCUUACAGUGAGCGGGAUGCCUACUGGGUGGAGAACCUUAUGGUCCAGGAGCUGGAGAACUUCAAUCCCCCCUUCAAGUUGUGUCUUCAUAAGCGGGACUUCAUUCCUGGCAAGUGGAUCAUUGACAAUAUCAUUGACUCCAUUGAAAAGAGCCACAAAACUGUCUUUGUGCUUUCUGAAAACUUUGUGAAGAGUGAGUGGUGCAAGUAUGAACUGGACUUCUCCCAUUUCCGUCUUUUUGAUGAGAACAAUGAUGCUGCCAUUCUCAUUCUUCUGGAGCCCAUUGAGAAAAAAGCCAUUCCCCAGCGCUUCUGCAAGCUGCGGAAGAUAAUGAACACCAAGACCUACCUGGAGUGGCCCAUGGACGAGGCUCAGCGGGAAGGAUUUUGGGUAAAUCUGAGAGCUGCGAUAAAGUCCUAGGUUCCCAUAUUUAAGACCAGUCUUUGUCUAGUUGGGAUCUUUAUGUCACUAGUUAUAGUUAAGUUCAUUCAGACAUAAUUAUAUAAAAACUACGUGGAUGUACCGUCAUUUGAGGACUUGCUUACUAAAACUACAAAACUUCAAAUUUUGUCUGGGGUGCUGUUUUAUAAACAUAUGCCAGAUUUAAAAAUUGGUUUUUGGUUUUUCUUUUUUCUAUGAGAUAACCAUGAUCAUAAGUCUAUUACUGAUAUCUGAAUAUAGUCCCUUGGUAUCCAAGGGAAUUGGUUGCAGGAUCCUCGUGGAUAUCAAAAUUCAUAGAUGAUCAAGUCCCUUAUAAGAGUGGCAUAGUAUUUGCAUAUAACCUGUGUACAUUCUCCUGUAUACUUUAAAUCAUCUCUAGAUUACUUAUGAUACCCAAUACAAUGUAAAUACUAUGUAAAUAGUUGUACUGUCUUUUUAUUUAUAUUAUUAUUGUUAUUUUUUAUUUUCAAAAUUUUUAAAACAUACUUUUGAUCCACAGUUGGUUGACUUCAUGGAUGCAGAACCCAUGGAUAUAGAGGGCCAACUGUAAUCUGUAGCAACUGGCUUAGUUCAUUAGGAAACAGCACAAAUGAACUUAAGAUUCUCAAUGACUGUGUCAUUCUUUCUUCCUGCUAAGAGACUCCUCUGUGGCCACAAAAGGCAUUCUCUGUCCUACCUAGCUGUCACUUCUCUGUGCAGCUGAUCUCAAGAGCAACAAGGCAAAGUAUUUGGGGCACUCCCCAAAACUUGUUGCUAUUCCUAGAAAAAAGUGCUGUGUAUUUCCUAUUAAACUUUACAGGAUGAGAAAUACUAGAGGGUGUAUUUUCAUGUGAUCUGGAUCUGUCUUUCUGGCUAUUAGAUAGGUUUCUCCAGCCAUAGUUACUUGAGAGAGUGAGUACACAGUGCAAGGUACAGUAAAUUAUGUAUUUCUGUAAUUUAACAAAAUAAAUACUCAGUUUAGGAGAAUUUGAAAGACACUUCCCACAUCCGGACUCUGGUCUUCCUCAGCCUCUAACUACCUUUUGAGUUCUAGUUAUUGUCCAAUCACUCUGACUCUCAGUUCCUGUUUUUUAGCCUAUAUCUCCUGCAUCUUGUUGCUUUUUCCUUCUUCGAAAAGUCUUGUUUUUAAUUCUAAAAAAGCCUGCCCUUUUUCCCCUUCUGAAUAUUUUAAAAAGUACAUGUGAGCUAAAUAGAUUUUUAAGCAAAUAUAUACCUAGAGUUUCCUCAUAAUGACUCAAAAAUAGUUUGAUACACAGUAAUUUAAAGGUAGAUACUACUACCAUAUGUUAAUUUUGCAAUCUAGGUAUAAUAAUACCACACAUUAAAUUUUGAUGCAACUUUCUUUGGUAAGCACUAUUUGCUGAUUCUAUGUAACUUUCUUAAGCUGGGAACCAUGUGAAAGGAAGUGAGCCUUUGACCCCUGCUCAAUUCUCAACCAGAACUGGGUGUAUGUGGUUAAUUGGGCACUAGAGUCAGAAAGACCUGGGUUAGUAGAUGUGUAAUCUUUGGCAAGUCAGUUGACAUGACCCAAAAAGUUUUUCUGUCUUUAAAAUAGGGAUGAUGAUCUCUAUAUCCUAAGAUACUGAGAGUAUGAAAUGUAGGAAUGUAAGUAAACCAUGAGCCUAAGCUCCUUGAUUCCCAUUUUCUCUGGAGGGGUGUUGAGGGCAAGAGUACCACGCCUAAGAGAAUGGGCACUAUGGGUUCGUGUGUGGGGUGAGGGUGAUGUCUGUAGUAGAUGUUAGCUAUUAUUAUUAUUUUCCAAGAAGAUAUUUCAUUCCCUUAUAUAUUAUGGCUUGUAAGUGGAUAUUUUUCUGUUAUGGAUACUAGCAGGGAUAUAAGGGAUCCUGCUGUUUGCAGAAAAAUACCACAAAGAAAUAUAUGCUCAUUAACUGCAGAACAAGCUUGUCCUUGGGGAACUCGCAUAGGGCUGCUGCUGUUUCACACGACCUCCCAGAAGAGUGUUAUGGAGGAAACGGUAGCCAGCCUUAAAAAAAAUCAGGCUUGGUGUAAUCCCAGCACUUUGGGAGGCUAAGGCAGGAGGAUUGCUUGAGUCCAGGAGUUGGAGACCAGCCUGGGAAACAUGGCAAAACCCUGUCUCUACCAAAAAAUACAAAAUAUUAGCAGGGCAUGGUGGCAUGUGCCUCUGGUCCUAGCUACUCGGGAUGCUGAGGUGGGAGGAUCACCUGAGCCCGGGAGGUCCAGGCUGCAGUGAGCUGUGAUUGCACCACUGCACUCCAGCCUGGGUGACAGAGGAAGACACUGUCUCAAAAAAACAAAAUGAAACAAAACAAACGAAAAACAAGUUUAGAGGAAGGAAACUUGAGAUUCCACAGACACCAAAUACAGUAAUGGACUUUCUGCUUUACUUCUCUGUUUCCAUGUUAAUUAUGAGAACAAGGUAGAUUUAACAUUGACUCGAUCUAUGUUUAAUUUCAAGAACUUAAAAUAGCAACUGAAAUAGCUUCAUAGAUAAUUGAUAGAUUUAAAAUAAUAUUUAAAAAAUAAUCUUUAGGACGGACGUGGUGGCUUAUGCCUGUAAUCCCAGCACUUUGGGAGGCUGAGGUGGGAGGAUCACCUGAGGUGUUGUGGUGCCUAUUCACAUUAAAGGUGGAUCUUCCUUUCCUAGUCCACUGACUCAAAUGUUAAUCUCCUCUGGCAACACCCUCACAUACACACCAGAAACUAUACUUUACCAGCUAUCCAGGCAUCUUUCAAUCCAAUCAAGUUGACACCUAGUAUUAGCCAUAAUACUCUCCAAUCUUUUUUCAGUGUACAUAUACACACUACUUUACAAAAUUGGGAUUAGAUUGUAAAUACUUAAAUUUUAUAAAGAAAAUGGCAUCUUCAUUUUUUUCUGAGGCUGUUUAGUGAUUAUCUGACAUUCCUGAACUCUGAGGGUCAUUGUGAAUCCCAUUCAGAUAAAUACUGGCUUAUUUGCCGAGAGUUCUAAAUGGUUCUGAAAGCUGCCAUUGUGGCUAUACAUAAAAGAUAAGUGGGAACUAAAUUAGAGAUCAGUUUAAGGGUUCUUUUUUUUGUUUAACAGGAGAAAAACUAAUUUUUUGUUAGUGCUUUAUCCAAAUGUGAAGUCUUUUAUUUGUCAAUAGACUAUAAGCUCAAGAAUCUUGUUUUAUCUCCCUACCCCUUGAACAUGCCUACUAUAUAGUAAGUAUUGAAUUAUUGGGAUGUUUUCAGAGUAGAGAAAUAAGCAAUUAAAAAUUCUAUAAUCUGGAUGCUGAAUCAAUCAUAAUGAGAGAGGAGAAAAUGAAAAAUCAGUUCGGUAGACAGCUAAGGCUAGUCUUCAGAGAAGCAGUCUGCCUGGAAAAUCACAGCUACAGGCAAAAAUAGAGCAGCCUGGGGAAAACUCAGACUGUACCUGCACAGAUAAGCAGGCAAGGUCCAGCACAGAAGCCUUUUGUUCUUUGUGUGAUUAGCAGGCUCCCAGGAAAAUGUUUUCUCCCCUUUUCAGAUAUGAACACGGGGGGAUCCAUGGGAGAUUGCACUGGAAACAGAGGGGGUUUACCUAAAAGAAACCCACAAUUACUCAAACAAGAAAAAACUAUGCUUUGUGCUUACCUAGAGACAUCUCACAGCUGUAUAGGUAGGUGGAGUUGUGCAGACAGGUUUUCAAAUAAGAGAAGUUACUCAAACAGCUACAGAGAUGAGAGGAGUUUCUUAUAAAAGCUUUUGCAUUCAGCUGUAAAAUGGCACCCCACUUGGGCUCUCCUCUCCACUGUGGAGAGCUUUCUUCUUUCACUUACUAAACUUUUGCUCCAACCUCACCCUUUGCAUUCAUGCUCCUUAAUUUUCUCAGUCAUGACACAAUAAGUUCAAAUAACACCUUAGACAAUGAGACAAUGGACCCUGACCUAUUUCAAUAAUACUGAAGCAUUGGGCAGUUUGAAAGAGGAAAGUUCUCAACAGUAAGAAAUUGUAGUGUGAGUUAUCUUAAUGAUGGACCUUUGAAUAGCAUUAAGUAUAGUGCCAAUAUCUGAACAAGGAAAAUAAUCAUUGUAUUUCCUUUCUACUUCAUACAAUUGUAAUGGCUUCAAGUAUUGCAGAGUAGAUGUCUGGUGUUAAAUGUAUACAGUGUUGACUAUUUUAAAAAUGACCAGUAAUUCAAAACAAAUUAAUUUUGAGAGUCCAACAUAUCAUUCAUGGGUUAAUUCUUUCUGACUGGUCUUCUCUAUUCAGUUAAUUUUGUUCCCUUCUGCCAGAUUAAUUUACUCUUUCAGCAAAUAUUUUUUGAGUGCCUCUUAUGUGCUAGGCAGUGCUCAAAGUGCAGGGGAUAUGGUAGGGAACAAAACAUAAAAUUCCUUGUCUUCAUGGAGGAGAAGACAAUAAAUUUAUGAUAGGAUUUCGGGUAUUGAGAAGUACUAUGAAGAAAAUAAAAGCAGAGUGCCACAAUGGAAUGACUGUGCACGUGUAUGUGUGCACGCGCACGCAGAGUGGAACAAAAGAAAAGUGAUUCUUCUUGCUUUAGUACAGCUGUUGCAUGGGUUUGAGCACUUUUGGCAGCUCCAGGAAACCCAAAGUACCUGUGGCCCAUUGAGAAGGUGUGGCACCUGCUGCCAGAGGCUUUGGGAGUAACCCACUUUCUACAGAAGAGCUCUGUGGUGCAGAAGCUGCCACAUGGUAACAAGCACAUGGAGCAGAAGACAAGCACAAUGUCCUUGACCAUAGAUUACUUAACGACUCCACCUACUUUAAAGAUGUUGAACUGAUGAGAAAGUAUUAGCUAUGGCUAAAUGUUGUGUGUGAGAAGUACUUUGCAAACCUCUGAAACACUUUACAGAUAUUGUUAUCAGUCAAACUGGAAGUAGAAUGUCCACAGUGCAGUGUAACAAAUGUGACAUGUGCAUGAGUUAAGAAACAGCUGUAAUGGGAAAGAUGAAAAAACAUGCUUUAUUUGUUUAUUCCAUUGUUCAGCUUCUCUUUAAAUUCUUUCCACAUGGACAAAUUGCUUGACAACAAAGUUUACUUAGUUUUCUAAACACUUGGGAUCAUCUCUAAAAUUAAAAAAAUUAAUAUUAAAUGUUGGACCAAGGAUUUCAACCAUGCAGUAUGUUGCUUCUGGGGUCUGCUGUCCUAUUCCAGCCCUAGUGAAUAGAUAAUGCCUUGAACUAUUCCUAUCACCACAGGUUGCCAGGCCACCAAAUAACGAAGCCAAUCCAGGAUUUGUCCAUACAGAAAAUGUGUGCGCUCCCAGCUAAAUCUCAGUUAAGGAGGUUGUUCUAUAUACAGCCAAGUAGCAGAAAUAUUCAUAAAUGUCAUUUGCAAAUAUAAUAAACAAUGUAAUGAAUGGGUAUUUCCUUUCUUGUUAAUUCUAUGUGCUCAAUUAAAAGCCCCUUAUGUGA